AGUCCCUCGGGCUCAUACCUAGUGCCUGCGGCAGGACAGCCAUGGCCGCCAACUCCACCAGCGACCUCCACACUCCCGGGACGCAGCUGAGCGUGGCUGACAUCAUCGUCAUCACUGUGUAUUUUGCUCUGAAUGUGGCCGUGGGCAUAUGGUCCUCUUGUCGGGCCAGUAGGAACACGGUGAAUGGCUACUUCCUGGCAGGCCGGGACAUGACGUGGUGGCCGAUUGGAGCCUCCCUCUUCGCCAGCAGCGAGGGCUCUGGCCUCUUCAUUGGACUGGCGGGCUCAGGCGCGGCAGGAGGUCUGGCCGUGGCAGGCUUCGAGUGGAAUGCCACGUACGUGCUGCUGGCACUGGCAUGGGUGUUCGUGCCCAUCUACAUCUCCUCAGAGAUCGUCACCUUACCUGAGUACAUUCAGAAGCGCUACGGGGGCCAGCGGAUCCGCAUGUACCUGUCUGUCCUGUCCCUGCUACUGUCUGUCUUCACCAAGAUAUCGCUGGACCUGUACGCGGGGGCUCUGUUUGUGCACAUCUGCCUGGGCUGGAACUUCUACCUCUCCACCAUCCUCACGCUCGGCAUCACAGCCCUGUACACCAUCGCAGGGGGCCUGGCUGCUGUAAUCUACACGGACGCCCUGCAGACGCUCAUCAUGGUGGUGGGGGCUGUCAUCCUGACAAUCAAAGCUUUUGACCAGAUCGGUGGUUACGGGCAGCUGGAGGCAGCCUACGCCCAGGCCAUUCCCUCCAGGACCAUUGCCAACACCACCUGCCACCUGCCACGUACAGACGCCAUGCACAUGUUUCGAGACCCCCACACAGGGGACCUGCCGUGGACCGGGAUGACCUUUGGCCUGACCAUCAUGGCCACCUGGUACUGGUGCACCGACCAGGUCAUCGUGCAGCGAUCACUGUCAGCCCGGGACCUGAACCAUGCCAAGGCGGGCUCCAUCCUGGCCAGCUACCUCAAGAUGCUCCCCAUGGGCCUGAUCAUCAUGCCGGGCAUGAUCAGCCGCGCAUUGUUCCCAGGUGCUCAUGUCUAUGAGGAGAGACACCAAGUGUCCGUCUCUCGAACAGAUGAUGUGGGCUGCGUGGUGCCGUCCGAGUGCCUGCGGGCCUGCGGGGCCGAGGUCGGCUGCUCCAACAUCGCCUACCCCAAGCUGGUCAUGGAACUGAUGCCCAUCGGUCUGCGGGGGCUGAUGAUCGCAGUGAUGCUGGCGGCGCUCAUGUCGUCGCUGACCUCCAUCUUCAACAGCAGCAGCACCCUCUUCACUAUGGACAUCUGGAGGCGGCUGCGUCCCCGCUCCGGCGAGCGGGAGCUCCUGCUGGUGGGACGCACUGGGAUACCCUCAACACCCCCAGCCCCUCAAAGCCGUCUCAGCUUCCUCCUGCCCGAAACACCACCAUUGGAGCGGUAUCUCCUAGGCCUCGUGGUCAUGGAUCUCUGGCUGGUCAUAGUGGCACUCAUCGGCGUGAGUGUGGCCUGGAUCCCCGUCCUGCAGGACUCCAACAGCGGGCAACUCUUCAUCUACAUGCAGUCAGUGACCAGCUCCCUGGCCCCACCAGUGACUGCAGUCUUUGUCCUGGGCGUCUUCUGGCGACGUGCCAACGAGCAGGGGGCCUUCUGGGGCCUGAUAGCAGGGCUGGUGGUGGGGGCCACGAGGCUGGUCCUGGAAUUCCUGAACCCAGCCCCACCGUGCGGAGAGCCAGACACGCGGCCAGCCGUCCUGGGGAGCAUCCACUACCUGCACUUCGCUGUCGCCCUCUUUGCACUCAGUGGUGCUGUUGUGGUGGCUGGAAGCCUGCUGACCCCACCCCCACAGAGUGUCCAGAUUGAGAACCUUACCUGGUGGACCCUGGCUCAGGAUGUGCCCUUGGGAACUAAAGCAGGUGAUGGCCAAACACCCCAGAAACACGCCUUCUGGGCCCGUGUCUGUGGCUUCAAUGCCAUCCUCCUCAUGUGUGUCAACAUAUUCUUUUAUGCCUACUUCGCCUGACACUGCCAUCCUGGACAGAAAGGCAGGAGCUCUGAGUCCUCAGGUCCACCCAUUUCCCUCAUGGGGAUCCCGAGGCCCCAAGAGGGGCAGAUUCCCCUCACAGCUGCACAGCAGCUCGGUGCCCAAGAACUGGCCAAGCCAGCAAAGCGGGAGCCCUGAAAAAUUAGGGGGGAAAUGGGAGAAAAUAAUGUGACAUUUCAAAAACAGCACCAAAGCAGUCAGCAUUGGAAGGAAAAUUAGAUUUCUGACGGACAUCCUGAUGUUGGUUUUACUGUUUUCGUUUUGAAUACACAGGCUGGGUCAGGAGCAGUGAGAUUUGCCAGCACUCAGGGUUCUAAGGGUCUUGGGCCAGCUCUGGAUGGAGGAAGAGCCCCACAUGCCCAGAGCAAGGCCCCCCAUUAAGGGACUGCAGCCACCUCCAAGGGCUCCUCCCUCCACCCACCGGCUCCCAAAUGCCAGAGGGAGCCUCUUCGCCCUCCCUCCCUGCCCACCAUCCCUCAACCAUCAGCCUGGCGUUCAAAGCCUUUCCAAGUCCCACCUCACUUUUCCCUCUCCCAAAGGUGCCCAGGCUCUGGGCAGGCCCUGCUCAUAUCCCUGAUCAUGGCACAUUCUCUGGAGGACCCUCCUGUUCUCGGGUAGGGGCCGUGCCCCACCUAGGUAGCCGUCCCAUGUGGGAUCCUGUAGGAUCUCUAAAACCUAGCUCUGGCCCCAACUUUCUGUCUGCCCUGGAGGUUUCUCAGCCUCCUGAGAGCUCUGCUGGGCCCCGGUCUGGGCAGAACCUGGGCCUAAACAAACAAGAGCCAGGGCAGCCAGGGUCUCUGCGUGGCUGGGCCCAGGGCUUGCCCUCAGAGCUCACCUGUCCAACAGAAGAGGAGUGUGCCUCCACCUUCCCUACUGCCCGCCCCUUUUUCAGGGUCUUAGGGCCUCUAGCCCUGUGGUGGGGUGCUGGGUGCCCCAGGUGGAGCUGAAGUCAUGGGGCUGUUGAGGAGUUGGUGUCCACCUGGAGUCUGUCCAGUGAGUUUAGGUCAACAGGUGUGCAGUCUGUCCUUCGAGGCUGAGCCACCUCCCAACAGCCUGAACAACUCCAGGGGCCUUUUGAGGGAGGGGCAGGCAGGCCCAGUGGGUGGUCAGCCCAAGGUGAACCCACCCACCAUGGCCAGGGUUCCUUAGGUUGAGCCUCCAGUGGGUGAAACCUGGGAGUCCUCAACCUUCCUGGCAGAUGGGGCCAUUGACAAGAGGAGGUGGGCGGGGCCUCCACAGACUCCGCCCUGUGGUGUCACACAGCUGGCAGCCAAUGGAAAGCAACCAGCCAGGAAGCCCCGGAGCUACCCUUGCUGGGUACCCUUGCUGGGGGACCUGGGCCAUCCCAGUUUGUGCAGAGCGGCCGGAGGCAGUUAGGAGCCCACGUUCAGUCCAAGGCCGUCCACUGAGCCCCGUGUGACUCUGACAGAGCUGGGGGUGUCCAUGUCCUCUCUGGACCUCAGUUCCUGUAAAAAGGCCCGUUGGCCAGAUCGGCCGCCGGGCUGCUCACAGGUGCACGGGCUGCACGUAACUCCGUGGGAAGAAGCCAACGCGCCCGCAGGACCGGCCCCGCCACCAGUGGGGGUCUGGGCGCUCCAGGACCUCAAUGAUGUCGCCACGGCGGAAGCUGAGCUGCGAGGGGUCCUGGGCUGAGAAGUCAAACUGGGCCUGGGCAAAGCAGGCCCCAGGUGACUGCAAGAAGAGGAGGUGGUUAGUAGGGUGCCUUCAGAAGCCCUGCAACCCACCCUCCCUCAGAGGCACCCAAGAGAAGUGAUUUGCCACAGGUGAGGAGGGGUCUCGGGCAGCACCGGAGUUGAACUUUAAGUCCAGAUCAAUGGUAGUGCCACCACUGGGCCUCCUGCUGCCCACACCCCUGCCUGUCUGCUGUGCAGAUGCUGCAUCUACAUAGAACACGGCUUUCCCAGCCGCCCAGCUGGGACAAUAGGGCUGGUGGGUCAGGGGACCUGAGUCCUGGUCCUUAGGGUGGGAUUUUGGUUAGGUCCCUGCUUCUCUUGGGAUCUUAUUUACCCGACUCUGCAGCAGCCAUGGUAGCUUUUGACUCCAGGCCACAAAGCCAUGAGAAUGGGCCUUAUAAACUGUAAAGUGACGUGCA